GAGUCGCACGGAGGGCAACCGUCGACGGGCUUAGCGCCUCAACUGUCGUUGGUGUAUUUUUCUGGUGUCACUUCUGUGCCUUCCUUCAAAGGUGGUGCUUUGUCCCUGUGGGUCAUCUGUACUGAUUGCGCCAAGCAAAGCAUUUGUUCUCCAAAUGUCAACUGUCAAGGAGCAGCUAAUUGAGAAGCUAAUUGAGGAUGAUGAAAACUCCCAGUGUAAAAUUACUAUUGUUGGAACUGGUGCCGUAGGCAUGGCUUGUGCUAUUAGUAUCUUACUGAAGGAUUUGGCUGAUGAACUUGCCCUUGUUGAUGUUGCAUUGGACAAACUGAAGGGAGAAAUGAUGGAUCUUCAGCAUGGCAGUCUUUUCUUUAGUACUUCAAAGAUUACUUCUGGAAAAG